AGUUGCCGGGCGGGGGAGGGCGCGUCCGGUUUUUCUCAGGGGACGUUGAAAUUAUUUUUGUAACGGGAGUCGGGAGAGGACGGGGCGUGCCCCGACGUGCGCGCGCGUCGUCCUCCCCGGCGCUCCUCCACAGCUCGCUGGCUCCCGCCGCGGAAAGGCGUCAUGCCGCCCAAAACCCCCCGAAAAACGGCCGCCACCGCCGCCGCUGCCGCCGCGGAACCCCCGGCACCGCCGCCGCCGCCCCCUCCUGAGGAGGACCCAGAGCAGGACAGCGGCCCGGAGGACCUGCCUCUCGUCAGGCUUGAGUUUGAAGAAACAGAAGAACCUGAUUUUACUGCAUUAUGUCAGAAAUUAAAGAUACCAGAUCAUGUCAGAGAGAGAGCUUGGUUAACUUGGGAGAAAGUUUCAUCUGUGGAUGGAGUAUUGGGAGGUUAUAUUCAAAAGAAAAAGGAACUGUGGGGAAUCUGUAUCUUUAUUGCAGCAGUUGACCUAGAUGAGAUGUCGUUCACUUUUACUGAGCUACAGAAAAACAUAGAAAUCAGUGUCCAUAAAUUCUUUAACUUACUAAAAGAAAUUGAUACCAGUACCAAAGUUGAUAAUGCUAUGUCAAGACUGUUGAAGAAGUAUGAUGUAUUGUUUGCACUCUUCAGCAAAUUGGAAAGGACAUGUGAACUUAUAUAUUUGACACAACCCAGCAGUUCGAUAUCUACUGAAAUAAAUUCUGCAUUGGUGCUAAAAGUUUCUUGGAUCACAUUUUUAUUAGCUAAAGGGGAAGUAUUACAAAUGGAAGAUGAUCUGGUGAUUUCAUUUCAGUUAAUGCUAUGUGUCCUUGACUAUUUUAUUAAACUCUCACCUCCCAUGUUGCUCAAAGAACCAUAUAAAACAGCUGUUAUACCCAUUAAUGGUUCACCUCGAACACCCAGGCGAGGUCAGAACAGGAGUGCACGGAUAGCAAAACAACUAGAAAAUGAUACAAGAAUUAUUGAAGUUCUCUGUAAAGAACAUGAAUGUAAUAUAGAUGAGGUGAAAAAUGUUUAUUUCAAAAAUUUUAUACCUUUUAUGAAUUCUCUUGGACUUGUAACAUCUAAUGGACUUCCAGAGGUUGAAAAUCUUUCUAAACGAUACGAAGAAAUUUAUCUUAAAAAUAAAGAUCUAGAUGCAAGAUUAUUUUUGGAUCAUGAUAAAACUCUUCAGACUGAUUCUAUAGACAGUUUUGAAACACAGAGAACACCACGAAAAAGUAACCUUGAUGAAGAGGUGAAUGUAAUUCCUCCACACACUCCAGUUAGGACUGUUAUGAACACUAUCCAACAAUUAAUGAUGAUUUUAAAUUCAGCAAGUGAUCAACCUUCAGAAAAUCUGAUUUCCUAUUUUAACAACUGCACAGUGAAUCCAAAAGAAAGUAUACUGAAAAGAGUGAAGGAUAUAGGAUACAUCUUUAAAGAGAAAUUUGCUAAAGCUGUGGGACAGGGUUGUGUCGAAAUUGGAUCACAGCGAUACAAACUUGGAGUUCGCUUGUAUUACCGAGUAAUGGAAUCCAUGCUUAAAUCAGAAGAAGAACGAUUAUCCAUUCAAAAUUUUAGCAAACUUCUGAAUGACAACAUUUUUCAUAUGUCUUUAUUGGCGUGCGCUCUUGAGGUUGUAAUGGCCACAUAUAGCAGAAGUACAUCUCAGAAUCUUGAUUCUGGAACAGAUUUGUCUUUCCCAUGGAUUCUGAAUGUGCUUAAUUUAAAAGCCUUUGAUUUUUACAAAGUGAUCGAAAGUUUUAUCAAAGCAGAAGGCAACUUGACAAGAGAAAUGAUAAAACAUUUAGAACGAUGUGAACAUCGAAUCAUGGAAUCCCUUGCAUGGCUCUCAGUAAGUAGCUAAAUAAUUGAAGAAAUUCAUUCAUGUGCAUAUGGCUAACAAAUUAUUGUUAGUGAGAGGUGUUUCUUAACAUCUACCUCAAGAACAUAUAGGGAAUUUAAUGAAUAAUGUUAUUUCAGUCUAUAGCCCAAGGAUCAAGUGGAAUAUUAGAAUGGAGCUUUAAUCGAGCACCCUAAACCAUCUAAUACAGCACAGUGAUUUAUUUAAGAAUAGCUUUUCUUAAAACAUGCCACUUUAAAACAAAACGGAUUUUUUUUUUAUACUUUAAGUUCUAGGGUACAUGUGCACAACGUGCAGGUUUGUUACAUAUGUAUACAUGUGCCAUAUUGGUGUGCUGCACCCAUUAACUUGUCAUUUACAUUAGAUAUAUCUCCUAAUGCUAUCCCUCCCUCCUCUCCCUACCCCAUGACAGGCCCCAGUGUGUGAUGUUCCCCACCCUGUGUCCACGUGUUCUCAUUGUUCAUUUCCCACCUAUGAGUGAGAACAUGCAGUGUUUGGUUUUCUGUCUUGGCAAUAGUUUGCUCAGAAUGAUGGUUUCCAGCUUCAUCCAUGUCCCUACAAAGGACAUGAACUCAUCCUUUUUUAUGGCUGCAUAGUAUAUAUGUGCCACAUAUUCCAUGGUAUAUAUGUGCCACAUUUUCUUACUCCAGUCUAUUAUUGUUGGACAUUUGGGUUGCUUCCAAGUCUUUGCUAUUGUGAAUAGUGCCACAAUAAACAUACGUGUGCAUGUGUCUUUAUAGCAGCAUGAUUUAUAAUCCUUUGGGUAUAUACCCAGUAAUGAGAUGGCUGGGUCAAAUGCUAUUUUUGGUUUUAGAUCCUUGAGGAAUCGCCACACUGUUGAACUAGUUUACAGUCCCACCAACAGUGUAAAAGUGUUCCUAUUUCUUCACAUCCUCUCCAGCAUCUGUUGUUUCCUGACUUUUUAAUGAUCGCCAUUCUAACUGGUGUGAGAUGGUAUUUCAUUGUGGUUUUGAUUUGCAUUUCUCUGAUGGCCAGUGAUGAUGAGCAUUUUUUCAUGUGUCUUUUGGCUGCAUAAAUGUCUUCUUUUGAGAAGUGUCUGUUCAUAUCUUUCACCCACUUUUUGAUGGGGUUGAUUUUUUCUUGUAAAUUUGUUUGAGUUCUUUGUAGAUUCUGGAUAUUAGCCCUUUGUCAGAUGGGUAGAUUGUAAAAGUUUUCUCCCAUUCUGUAGGUUGCCUGUUCACUCUGAUCGUAGUUUCUUUUGCUGUGCAGAAGCUCUUUAGUUUAAUUAGAUCCCAUUUGUCAAUUUUGGCUUUUGUUGCUAUUGCUUUUGGUGUUUUAGUCAUGAAGUCCUUGCCCAUGCCGAUGUCCUGAAUGGUAUUGCCUAGGUUUUCUUCUAGGGUUUUUAUGGUUUUAGGUCUAACAUUUAAGUCUUUAAUCCAUCUUGAAUUAAUUUUUGUACAAGGUGUAAGGAAGGGAUCCAGUUUCAGCUUUCUACAUAUGGCUGGCCAGUUUUCCCAGCACCAUUUAUUAAAUAGGGAAUCCUUUCUCCAUUUCUUGUUUUUGUCAGGUUUGUCAAAGAUCAGAUGGUUGUAGAUGUGUGGUAUUAUUUCUGAGGGCCCUGUUCUAAACCAAAACAGAAUUCUUUAAAGUAUUUAGAUAAUUUAUUUAAAGUACAGUUGUUAUAUAUUUGAAAAUGCAAAUGUCUGCUCUUAAAUUGUGAGAUUAUGCUAUUUAGAUUAUUAAAAAGUGCAUUUUUUUCUUGUUAAAUAUAGUAGGAUUCAUUUUUUCCCAUUAUUAAAGUAUAAAAAUGUAUACUAUUGUUCAAUUAUAGGUAUUGGUUCAAUCAAUAUAGGGGCACAAAUUAUAUUGUCUAGGAUUCUCUUUAUAGCAUUAUAACUAUUGAUAAGGCUUUUGUUUUAAUAAAAGUGGCAACUUGAGGUUAUGCUCUUCAAAUCAACAUAGUUGGAUAAUACUUUGUGAAUCAUCAGUUUUGUAAAUUAAUGGUUUCUUUUGAAACUGUGUUGCAUGCUAAGUAUAUAUCUUUUAAUUUGUAUCAGUAUAUAGAAGUGGUAAUUAAAAAAUUAAGACUUUAGGUAUGCCAUAAUCCUAAUUUGCACAUGUAACCUUAGUUUUAAUUUCCUUACGUUUUGAAUUUUUAAUGACUAAGCGAUAAUUUAUUUCUUAGUGUUUUCUUGUAUUGCCAUAUAGACAGAGUGAAUAGAGGAGAGAAACAUGGGAAAUUGAUAGAAGAAUGUUACACUCCUAUUAUUGAAUUUCAUAACUACUUAUGGAAUGAAUUUACACUUGAUAAGGAGUACUUAGAAGAAAACUUUCUGAAUCUGGGUAAUUAAGUGAAAGUAAAAAUAAAUAGAUAAGUAAAUAAAAUAAGCACAUAGAGUACUUUUUAAAGGCUUAUGUGUCCUCUCCUCCCAGAAAUUGAUAUUGAGAUAUUCCUGUAUCAUCUGAAAGUGACUAUUGUUAUUUCUUUUAGAGAAUUAAUUUUAUUUCUAUCAACACAUAUUUAUUGAACAUACGCCAUAUGCCUUGAAUUGAGAGAGAUACUGUGAAGAUACAAAAAAGAUAAAGGCUUGGAAAAUUGUGGAGGAUGUAAUAGAAAUUUACUGUUUAAAAAUUGUUUGUACUCAAGCCUGUUUAGCUCAGUUAUUUAGGGCUUCUAAACAAUAUUCCUUUAUUUUUGAGAAUUUUUGGAGAAAAAGUGACAAGCCCCAAAUCUGGAAAAGAGUAUGAUUGAUUUACAAUAGGAGACGUGGAAGUCAUAAGCCUCUGAAUUUAAAUAUUAAAUGUAGUAUCUCUGGCAGAUGAAACUAUAGAGGACUUUUAUUUAGUCAUAUAUUUUUAGUGUUUGAGUCUUAUAUUACAUUUUUAAUCAUAAAAACCUUGAGUGGUAGUGGAUAACUUUGUGAAGAUAAGUUAUGCCACACAAACAGGAUACUGUGUAUUUUUCCUGUGAGAAUAAUUGACAUUAUAGAGAAGGGAUAUGGCAUAGAUACAUUUGCGUUUUCACAGACUUUUUUUUAAAAUUUGAAAUAUAACACAUAUUAAGAAAAGUAUAUAUCUCAAGUGACAGUUUGGUGAAUUUGUCACAAAUUGAACACAUCCGUGUAAACAACACCCAGAUAAAGGCCCAGAGCAAGCUUUCAUAGUCUUUUGAUUCUGUGUCAUAAUAAAAAAUUCUCGUUAAAACUGUAGAUUGAUAGGAACAUAUUCACACAGAGUUGUUGACUGAGGGAAAUUUCAAAUGAGGUGCUGCUUACUUCUCUCCUGCCAAUAAUUUAAUGAAAGAAAGAACAUCAUCUUAUUUUUAAUGGUUGUGUGGGGAACUGGGUUCAGCAUUUUUGCUUGACAGCCUUGAGAUAAAAUAAAUCCAUAAGGAAAAAGCCCACUUCUGUUUCUUUUCAUCCCAGAGAGAUUAAUGGGCAAUAUAUGAGUGUAAGAUACUGGAAAAGUCUGUUGAGAAACCUAGUGAAAUCUCAUUCUCUGAAAAGUUGGGGGAUUACAGGUGCUAUCGAAUGCAUCAUACCUAAGGGUUAGAUGAAAUGACUUCCAAGAGUUUGGCCCUAUUAAAUCUGUUAAGAGGUUUAUAAUGCCAGCAGGUGAUGAAAUGAAAUUUGGAUGCCUUAGUUUCAGUAUUUUCAGAAUUUAUCAUAUUUUUUCAAUAAAUGUUUAUAAAUCAAAGUAUGUCAGAUGCUUUAUUCCCUAUAUGAUCUGUCUUUCCUGGACUAUUCUGGACUCUUCCUAUUGAUCUCUCAUUUGCUACCUUGAGACCAUUUCUCUCACAGCAGCCAGAGAAAUCUGCUCAUAAUGUAAAUCUCAUCAUGCUAAUUCCUCAGGUAAAAAACCUCCUGUGGAGGACAUAUUCAUCUGGUAAUGUUGGAAGAAGACCCUACCAUAUGGCUUUCUGCAAAAAAGACCACUAUACUACCUGUUUGGAAUACAAAAAGUAACUGACUGAAAUUACUGGACAGGAAGAACAGAUGCUAGUUGAGAAAGAGAAGAGGGGAGCUGGGAGCCUGAGGAGAAGGCUUUUAGUCUAGGGCUAAGUGCAGUAGGUAUAGGGAAGGACAGUAAGGUAGGGCAGGGAUGUCAGUGGGAAAACUAUGGGUCUCUUCACCAGGAAAACUGGAAAAUUGAAGCUAGGGAAACCUUGGCCACUGAAGAGAGUGGAAGAAUCCUGCAAGGGAAAGAGCCAAGAAAGGGUACCCAGAUUCUGUCUGAAAUCUGAAUAAUUCCUGUGUGUCACAGACUCAGAGCAGCCAAAUGAAGGGCAAAAGAUCUGAACUGAAACUGGAGUUGCUGCCCAAUAAACAGAACAGUUCAAGUUAAGCAAAGAUAAUUGCUUCUUACAACAAAACCAUUCUCAUUUUAGAAAAAUAACAGAAUUUAGGAUCUUCACAAUGUAACAUUUAUGAUGUUCAGGAUACAGUUCUAAAAUUAUCCAGCAUAGAAAGAAGGUCAAAGAAACCAAAUGCUGGUUUAUAGAAUAGGAGCUUUAGGCCAGGUGUGUGGUGCACACCUAAUCCCAGCAUUUUGGGAGGCUGAGGUGGGAGGAUCAUUUGAGCCCAGAAGUUCAAGACCAGCCUGGGCAACAAAGCAAGACCCCAUCUCUUAAAAAAAAAAAAAAAAAGCUAGGUGUGAUGGCAUGGUGGCAUGUUCCUGUGGUCCUAGGUACUUGGGAGGCUGAGGCAACACAGCGAGACUCUGUCUCAAAAAAAUAAAAAAUAAAAACAAAAAAA